AGACGCUCCCCGGCGCCGGGCAUGGGCGCCGCCGCCGUCGGUCCCCGAGCCGGAUUCCGCGAGCGGGUGGGUGAGCGCGGGGGGCCUCGGCCCCUCGGACCCCGGGCACCCGCGGGCGGGGGAUGGUGGCCGCGUUUGCACCCCCGCCCUAGUGCAUGUUCCCGCUGGAAUCGUUCCACGACCGCUCCCCCUCCCACCCGCGGGACAAAGGGCGGGGGCGGGGGGGGCGCACCCCCACGCGUGACCUUUCCCCGUACUGCGCACGCGCCCAGCCCCCACCACCGGGGGACGGUCCGCCCGCCCACGCGAGUGCGGGGGAGGGGUGUGGGGGCCCCGAAGGUAGAGGAGGCAGCGCGCACGGGCUGGACCUCCUCCUACCCUGGGAAGUUGGGGCAGUUUCCCCCUGCACCUGCCUCUUCCUUAGGCCUGGCAGUGGCCCGCGAUGAGAGAGGGUCCUUCCCCUUCAGGCUAGGUGUCCCUGGUCAGGCGACCCCUUGGGGCACCCAGCAAUUUAGGGCUUCAGCUUCCUUUUCCUUCGAUACCCAGGAGCCCACGUCCCCAGCUCACUUCUCCCCCAGGACCUAGGCGGCUGGGCCCCCUGCCCCUGACUCCAGGAGCCCAGGAGUUUGAAGCCCAGGCGCGUUUUGCCUCAGUCCUGGGGUCCAGGCUCCCUCCUCCCUCAGACCAGGGGUCCAGGCCAGAAGGUCCCUCCUGUCUCACUUCACCUCCCCCAGGAUGGACCCUCCAGUCCAUCUGCGUCUCUCCAUUUGUGGCUGCCGUUUCUGUCCAGUGCCCCUGAGGCCCUCGGCUGCUGGGGUCCGUAGGAAGCCGCGCCAUGAAUGACCGGAGCAGUCGGAGGCGGACAAUGAAGGACGAUGAGACCUUCGAGAUCUCCAUUCCCUUCGAUGAGGCACCCCACCUAGACCCACAGAUCUUUUACAGUCUGAGCCCCUCUCGGAGAAACUUCGAGGAGCCUCCGGAGGCUGCGUCCUCCGCCCUGGCUCUGAUGAACAGCGUCAAGACCCAGCUGCACAUGGCUCUGGAGAGGAACUCCUGGCUGCAGAAGCGCAUCGAGGACCUGGAGGAAGAGAGGGACUUCCUGCGGUGCCAGCUGGACAAAUUCAUCUCUUCUGCUCGGAUGGAGGCAGAGGACCACUGCCGGAUGAAGCCUGGGCCCAGGCGGAUGGAGGGGGACAGCCGUGGUGGGGCUGGGGGCGAGGCCUCGGACCCUGAGUCAGCAGCCUCCUCCCUCAGCGGAGCGUCCGAAGAAGGCAGCGCCAGUGAGAGGAGGCGGCAGAAGCAGAAGGGAGGUGCUAGUCGGAGGCGCUUUGGGAAGCCCAAGGCCCGGGAGAGGCAGCGAGUGAAGGACGCCGACGGGGUCCUCUGCCGGUACAAGAAGAUCCUGGGCACCUUCCAGAAGCUCAAGAGCAUGUCGCGGGCCUUCGAGCACCACCGCGUGGACAGGAACACCGUGGCGCUGACCACGCCCAUCGCCGAGCUGCUCAUUGUGGCCCCCGAGAAGCUGGCCGAGGUGGGCGAGUUCGACCCCUCCAAGGAGCGCCUGCUCGAGUACUCCCGCCGCUGCUUUCUGGCCCUGGACGACGAGACGCUCAAGAAGGUGCAGGCGCUCAAGAAGAGCAAGCUGCUGCUGCCCAUCACCUACCGCUUCAAGCGGUGAUCGCACCACGCCUCCGCGCCUCCACCCGGGCCUUCCUCCCCCGUGGACCCCGGUGGAUGACCUGCCCCUCUCCCCGCCGCGCCCCUGCCCCUCCUCCUCGCUCCCUGGGUUGGGGGCUCCCUUAGCCGGGCCCCCAAGCGCGACGGCCCCGGACCGGCCGCGGCCCCUUCCCGAACGCCGGCACCCCCUUCCGCUUGGGCUGCCCAGCCCUGUCCUCGCCGGGCCCCUUCCUCCUGGAAAACCAGGCAGGCGGGUGCCCCCCCCUCGAGUGGGGGACUGUACAGACCCCGUCUCCGCCCUGGCCCCGCGGAGGAGCUGCCCACCUGAUUCCCGGACAGACCUCCCCAACUCCGCGUGAGACAGAGAAUUAUUCAGAUAAUUUAAAUUAAAAAACGACGUGAAAAUUUGGAAUAAA